AAUUGUCGGGAGGGGUUUACUCUCUGAUCUGAACUGUGGCAGGGCGAGUUGAGAGGUGAAGAUGGCUUGUAGGAGAUGGCCCAGGCUGAUGGGGUAGGGAAGGUGGUGGCUACAGAGGACUGAGGAGGAGAGCAGAAAAUCUUCAACCACAGCAGCCAGGAGGCUUGUAAUAUUUCAGAGGCAAUCCAGCUUCCUAGCAGCAACUACUGUUUGUAAAUCACACACUACCUCUAAUGCUACAUCCAAAGGUAGACACACAAUGGGUUUAGUUUCCAUUUUUGUAGAAUUAAGUUUACAAACCCCCACCACCAAAGUAAGAAAUCUUGCAGGGAUUAUAUUGUAAAUCUAAUGUCAAACCAGACCUAUUGUAUCUAGUUCAGUUCAUUGAAGAUAUUUAGUCAUAUUUGUAAUCCACUGAAGGACUGAGGAUGAGGCUGGUUCCCAGGACAGGGUUCCAGAUUGUGUCUGUAAUUAAAUGAGAUAAUAUAUGAAACUGCCUAUAGCUCAAGAUCUGACACCUCUUAGUGAGCCUCAUUUUCUCCAUCUGUGAAAUGGGGAUCACAACUCUUAACUUUGCUAGCUCAUGAAAGGAAGAGAUAUAUUCUGAAAGAUAGGCCCCCUUGAAGAAUUACCCCUAUGAGAAAAUUUGAUAAAUUUUAAUAAAUAUCAUAAAUAUCAGCAUGUUAGUUUCCAGAGUGAGAAAUGUUCACAAAGAGCCCUUAUCAUAGGGGAAAAAAAGUCUUCUUGGGAAUCCAAAAUAAUCAGAGGGUUGCCUGGUGUCCCAGAUAAUAAACAUCAGAAAUCAGCUAGAGACCUCAAGACCCAGGGACAUUGAUCCCAAACCAGGCUCUCAGAACACCUGUGCUGGGAGAUGCUCCACAAAAGAGAAAGUUCAUGAUUACAUAAGUUUGAGAAAUACCACAUACUCUAAUCCCUGUUGGGGAUUCACAAUACAGAUUUGUGUGUGGUGCGUGCUAGCCACCAUGGCCAGAGCCUGCUACAUAAACUAGACUAUUCCUAAACUAAUAGCAAGAAAAAUAAUACCCAGGCUAGAUAUUUAUAUCAACCGGUCAGCAACAUCACAUUCCUAUAGACCAGUGAUUCUCUAACUUGAGCUUGCAUCAGAAUCAUCUGGAGGGCUUGUUAAAACACAAAUUACUGGGACUUGCUUCCAAAAUUGCUGAUUUAACAGAUCUGGGAGGAGUGCGGUGGGGAUAAGAAUUUGCAUUCCUGACAGGUGAUGCUGCUGCUGCUGGUCCUGACCACAUUGGGAGAACCACUGCUCUAGACAAAUCUUUACGGAAAGGCAAUAACAAACAGAAGGUGGUGGCAGGGAGAAGCAGGAAGAGCUAGCAAGGAAGCAUGCAAGGUUUGUCCUGUCACUCAACCAAACUAUGGAGAAAAAAGCCACCACCACUGUUUACAUAAAUGAGACUUAUACCAAAAUAAACUUGAAGAGAGAAGACAUAGCAUUGCAAAAAAAAUGUAUUCAAGAGGCAGAGGAGCUAAUGGAAAAAGAAAGGGCAGAAUAUCUAAUAAGAAAACAAGAGUUGACUGCACAGAUUAAUGAAUUUGAAAAUACCCGUGAAGUAAAGAGAAUGGAGACUUAUCAAAAGAAGAAAGAAUUGGAUAAAUUACAAACUAAAAUGUCAAAAAUAAAAGAAACAGUUACUGUUUCCGCAGCGGUUCUUAGUGAUCACAAUUUAGAGAUAGCACGACUACACGAAUCAAUAAGGUAUUGGGAACAAGAGGUCAGUGAGCUAAAGAAAGACCUUGCAAUUCUGGAGGCGAAACUGUGUUUUUUCACAGAUAACAAAGAAAAACUAGAUGAUAUAUCUAAUGAUGAAAAAAAUGAAUUCCUGAACAAGAUAAAACAGCUGGUUGAAACACUGCAUGCUGCUCGUAUGGAAUACAAAGACCUACGAGAGAAAAUGAAAACUCUUGCCAGACAAUAUAAGAUUGUUUUAAGUGAGGAAGAAAAAGCUUUUUUGCAAAAACAAAAGAUUCAUGAUGAAAAUCAGAAACAGCUGACAUUUAUUUCUCAGAAAGAAUACUUUCUGUCACAAAAGAGAGUAGACAUCAAAAAUAUGGAAGAAGGACUCAUCACACUCCAGGAACUUCAACAAGCAACAAAAACAGUGUAUCAGCAACAAAUCAAAAUCCUGAGUGCUAACCUGGAAAGAGAAAGUCAGAGAUGUGUUAUAACUCAGUGGAAAAUGGCUUGCUUGAGAAAAAAGCAUGCACGUUGGACAGCCAAGAUAAAAGCUGAAAUACAAGCUAUUACAGAAAAAAUUCAGAAUGCAGAAGUUAGACGAAUUGAAUUACUUAACGAGACCAGUUUCAGACAACAGGAGAUCAGUGGAUUUGUGGCACAGAUUGAAAAACUUACAACAGAAUUAAAAGAAGAGGAGAAAGCAUUUGUUAACAAAGAAAAAAUGUUAAUGAAAGAGUUAAGCAAGUAUGAGGAAAUAUUUGUUAAGGAAACACAAAUUAACAAAGAAAAGGAAGAAGAACUAGUUGAGUAUCUUCCACAACUUCAGGUGGCAGAACAAGAGUAUAAAGAGAAAAGAAGAAAGUUAGAAGAGCUCAGUAAUAUUAUUACAGCACAAAGACAGGAGGAAGAUUUACUGAACAAUCACAUUUUUCUGUUUACAAGGGACUUUUCAAGAUACAUUAGCAACAUGCAGGAAGAUGUAAAACAAGAAUUACAACAAUUACGAGAUCAAGAAAGCAAAAAAAACAAAGAUCAUUUUGAAACUCUAAAGAACUUAGAAAAUGGAUUCUAUAUAAAUGACCAAAAAGCAGAUCUUCUGCUCCUGGAAAAUAAAAAAUUAAAAGAAUAUAUUUUAUACUUGAAGAAUAACAUAGAGAAAUACAGAGAAGGACAAGAAGCCCUCAUGCACACCUCAAGCGACUUGUCUCGGCAACUAAUAGCUCAGGAGGCACAAUAUAAGGAUUUGUGGGCUGAAUUUCAGACCACAGUUAAGAUCUUGGUGGACAAUGGUGAAGAGACCUUGCAAGACAUAAACAAUCUAACAGACAAGCUGCGUGAAAGAGAUGAAAAAAUGCAGCAUGUCAGUACAUGGCUACGAGGGAGUCUUGAAGGGCUGCGUUUGCUUGUGGAACAGGAAUCACCAAUGGACCUUCUUAAGAAGAAGAAACACAUUCGUACAAGGGUUCAUUUCCCAGUGGUUAAAUGUACUGAGAAAAAUACAUUAACAAAGUAACUCAAGGAUACAACUGCUGUGAAUUCAAAAGACAGACUACUACAGGAAAAGUGAGUGCACUUACUUUCAUAUUUUGCAGCUGUUAAUAGAAGUCUUAAACAUUUAAAAUUUAACUAAUUCACACAACCUCCACCAAGUAUCAGUAAAUAAACUUCUAAACAAUAAAAAUGGA